GUUGGUGCCGCGGCCACUGGCCCAGCCGAUGGGUCGGGACACACGCUCGCGCUCGCGGUCCGCGGGUCGCCGGGGCCGAAGGCGGCAGAGUCAGAGCGGGAGCCGAAGUCGGAGCAGGAGCCAUGGGCGGCGAAACCGACGGCGCCGGGAGGACGAGGGACGGCGCAGACGGAGGCGGCGGAGCCGGGAGCGCAGGUCAGAUUCAGAGGAAGAGCGGUGGCAGCGCUCAGGGAUGCGAAGCCGGAGCCCCCCGCGGCCCAAGUGGCACUCAAGAGAUGGGUCCUCUCAGUCGGACUCAGGAGAGGAGCAGUCACGGGGCCAGUGGGCUCGCCGGCGACGGCGCGCACGCUCGUGGUCUCCUAGCUCCUCAGCAUCCAGCUCCGCGUCUCCAGGGCGAUCCCAGAGCCCCCGGGCGGCCGCGGCUGCCCUGAGCCAGCAGCAGAGCCUGCAGGAGCGGCUGCGGCUGCGGGAGGAGCGGAAGCAGCAGGAGGAGCUGAUGAAGGCCUUCGAGACGCCCGAGGAGAAGCGCGCACGGCGGCUGGCCAAGAAGGAGGCCAAGGAGCGCAAGAAGCGGGAGAAGAUGGGCUGGGGUGAGGAGUACAUGGGCUACACCAACACCGACAACCCCUUCGGAGACAACAACCUGCUGGGCACCUUCAUCUGGAAUAAGGCCCUGGAGAAGAAGGGGAUCAGCCACCUGGAGGAGAAGGAGCUGAAGGAGCGGAACAAGAGGAUCCAGGAGGACAACCGGCUGGAGCUGCAGAAGGUGAAGCAGCUGCGGCUGGAGCGGGAGCGGGAGAAGGCCAUGCGCGAGCAGGAGCUGGAGAUGCUGCAGCGCGAGAAGGAGGCAGAGCACUUCAAGACAUGGGAGGAGCAGGAGGACAACUUCCACCUCCAGCAGGCCAAGCUGCGUUCCAAGAUCCGCAUCCGGGACGGGCGGGCCAAGCCCAUCGACCUGCUGGCCAAGUACAUCAGCGCUGAGGAUGACGAUCUGGCCGUGGAGAUGCAUGAGCCCUACACGUUCCUCAACGGCCUCACCGUGGCCGACAUGGAGGACCUGCUGGAGGAUAUCCAGGUCUACAUGGAGCUGGAGCAGGGCAAGAACGCCGACUUCUGGCGGGACAUGACCACCAUCACCGAGGACGAGAUCUCCAAGCUCCGCAAGCUGGAGGCCUCGGGCAAGGGGCCAGUGGAGCUUUGUGUUCCCCGGAGGUGGAGUUCACUCAGCCAUCCUGUCCCUCCAGUGGUCUCCUCCGUGGGGCACAUUCUCCCGUAACCUCAGAGAGGCAGGGCAGUUCUCCAGCAUCAGAGGUGUGUCCGUUAAGGGUCUUGGUGUGCUCCUGCUGGUGGCAGCGGGGCUGGGCAAAGACUUCUGGGUGCAGUACAUUUUCCUUCAGAAGCCGCAGACCCUACCCACCGGCUGCAGGAAGCCUGGGAGGCGUUUCCAGCGUUGCCCUAGGCCCCGCCCUCUCCUGUAAGACUGGGAGGCGUUUCCAGCGUUGCCCUGGGCCCGGCCUCUCCUAUAAGCCUGGGAGGCGUUUCCAGCGUGCCCCACUGCCCUAGGCCCCGGCCUCUCCCAUCCCUUCCAUGGCCUUCUGCCUCCACCACGUCGCUCAGCCCUCCUUUCCCCUCACGCGUUACAGUUGGGGACCCCAGGUGGCUUUGGUGUCUUCCGAGGGAGUUUGUUUCUGAUUCUCCUUUCAACAUGGUUUCCAGGAGUAGGGAACCGAGGGGUCUUGACUUUGCUGUCCCCCUGGAGACCCACAGAGCCCCUGUCCUGGAUCUUCUUAAAUUAAUUGGGGUUUUCCUUUUACUUUUCAUUUUUCAGAGACAAGGUCUCGCUCUGUCGCCCAGGCGAGAGUUGAGUGGCGCGAUCAAGGCUCACUGUAGCCUCGACUUCCUGGGUUCAGGUGAUCCUCCCACCUCAGCCUCCCUAGAAGCUGGGACUACAGGCGCUCACCAUCACACCCAGCUAUUUUAUUUUUUGAGAAGGAGUCUCACUCUGUCACCAGGCUGGAGUGCAGUGGUGCGAUCUCUGCUCACUGUGACCUCUGCCUCCCAGAUUCAAGCGAUUCUCCUGCCUCAGCUGCCCAAGUAGCUGGGAUUACAGACGCGCGCCAUCACGCCCAGCUAAUUUUUGUAUUUUUAAGGAGACAGGGUUUCACCAUGUUGGCCAGGAUGGUCUCAAUCUCUUGACCUCAUGAUCCUCCCACCUCAGCCUCCCAAAGUGCUGGGAUUACAGAAGUGAGCCACUGUGCCCAGCCACUUCUGAAAAUUUUUUGUAGAGAUGGGGUCUCACUGUGUUGCCCAGGCUAGUCUUGAACUCCUGGCCUCAAGCAAUCCUCCUGCCUCACCUCCAGAAGGGCUAGGAUUAAAGGCAUGAGUGACUGCAUGCUUUUUCUUUUUAAUUUUUACAAAAUUAAAGUUUUUUUAUUAUUUCUGUAGGUUAUUGGGGAACAGGUGGUGUUUGGUUACAUGAAUAAGUUUUUUUGUUUUUUGAGACGGUGUCUUGCUCUCUUGCCAGGCUGGAGUGCAGUGGUGUGUUCUCAGGUCACUGCAACCUCUGCCUCCUGGGUUCAAGCAAUUCCCCUGCCUCAGCCUCCCAAGUAGCUGGGAUUACAGGCACCUACCACCACACCUGGCUAAUUUUUUGUAUUUUAGUAGAGACAGGGUUUCACGAUGUUGGCCAAGAUGGUCUUGAUCUCCUGACCUCGUGAUCCACCCACCUCAGCCUCCAAAAGUGCUGGGAUUACAGGCGUGAGCCAUCGUGCCCGGCCGUUUACAUGAAUAAGUUCUUUAGUGGUGACUUGUGAGAUUUUGGUGCACCUAGCUUUUUCUAGGAAGUUCUAACCCUACAGGAGGUUGUGCAGUAGAAAACGGGUGUCAUCCCAGCUCAGCUUCAUUAGCCUCCCACCCUGUGUAGGGCCUGGCCUUUCCCCCACGCAGCCCCAGGGCCCUUGGCCUGCACCCCCAGCCUCUAGCAGCUGCUGGGACCCCCUAAACCCCCGGGCCCCCUUGUGGGCAUUCGGGAGGCAUCCAGACAUGCAGCAGCAUGUCCAGACCCGGCUUUCUAUAGACGCUGACCUGGCGGCACCUGGCCUGGCUUCCUGGGAGCCUCGCGGCUGGGCUCUUCUGCUUGGGUUUCAGUGUUCGUGGUAGCCCCGCCUGUCUGGGCACGGCCGCGCUGUGCUUGGCUGGGGCUGCCACGGAUUCCAGUGCCACUUAGCGCCCAGCAAAGGGGCUGCAGCUCUGGGUGCCGAUUCCAGGGUCCCAGGUGAUUGGCUGGAGGGGACUCGGGUCCGUCUAGACUCUAUCCAGUCCCCUGUGGUGUAGGUGUGGGCCUCUUGACCCUCUGUCCGCCAGCGGGGACUGGAGAAGGCAGGUCUCGAGCAGGGUGCCUGCACUGGUCACCCCCGCCCAGUGUGUCACCAGCAGCUAUGCACCAAGCUCCCUGUGGGCCCAGCAUGGCACAGGGAACAGCAGCAGCCAGCCCCAUUGCCCGCCUCGGGAAGCUGCCAUCGCUGGAUGGUCAGGGAGGGCUUCCUGGCGGAAGGGAUGUUCUCACUGAGCAUGGAGGAUGCGAGGAAUUCAGGAAGCGAAUGGGACAGAGAAGGAUGGGUAGCUGGCAGGAAGCACAGUGCGUGCAAAGGCCCAGAGGUGGCAGGGGUUCGGCAUGGGCAGCAAGGGGCAGGGUUGCGAGGUGAGGCCAGACCCAGCGGGGUGGGUGGAAGUGGCCUGAGAGCAGCACUGAGGCCGCCGGGAUGCCACGUGGUGUGGGGCAGAGCACGCGGAGUCAGGCUAGGCUCCAGCCUCCCAGCACCCCACUCCCGCCCUCAGCAGCCUCCCCGUCUAUCGAGGAGGGACUUGAGCCUCGGGCCCCUGGGCCAGUGGUAGAUGCCAGACAGACUCCAUGUAGGAUGGGGGGCGGCGGUGGGGAGCUGUUUGUCCUGGGGCGGGCCCAGGACUUCCCCAGGGGCCAGCAGGGUGGCCUUCUUUGCUAGGCUUCACAGAGGGAAACUAAGGCCCAGAAAGGGCAGGCCACUUGCCCACAGUCACACAGCCCAGGCUGGCAGAGAAGAUCUGAAUUCCAGAGAGCCUGGCUACCGAGCACACCCCCCAACCCCCUCAUGGACUGCCCAAGGCCAGGGCAGAGUUGGGCCAGGUUGGUGGGCCGGGCCCACAACUAGGGUUCCCAGACCCACAUAUCAGACUCACCUGGGGAGGGGCAUUCUCAGGGCCAGUCCUGGCCUCCCCCACGCUGGGGGCCUGGGCCUCCAGGUCAAGGCCUCAGCAACUGCAUCUUAACGUGGCUCCCAACCUCCGCCCACCCCCUCCCCUCCGCUGUGGCCAGGGUGGGGACAACCUGAGACCAGGGAGGUGGCGGGACUGGAUGGGACCCCUGUGGGGGAAGAGGAGGGGAGGGGGACCCCCCCAUGGCAGGGGAGGAGGCCCUGAUGGGGUGGAGGAGCACGUAGGAAAUGUGGAACCGCCCCCCCAUGCCCCCACCCCG